CUUUGAGCGGAAGUUGGAUCACUGAAGCGCCAAAAAAGAAUUUAGGGGAAGACCUGAUUUUCGCUUGAGGCAUUUUUGCGGCGCUGUGCGCUACAGACACCUUCUGGAAGCUGCGGUGGGGAAACUGAGUUUCCCGAGCCGUUGAGACAGAUGGGGUUCAGCACCGCGCGGGGACGACAGGAAAGCUGCGGCUGAAGAGAACUGCGGACUUGGCAGGAGUCGCCUGAGGAGCUAAGAUCCCGGAGACUCUUAGCCCCGUGGUGCUUCUCUACGGGAGGGAGGGAGGGAGAAUCCGGCCGGACAGAUCUGCGCGUAUCCUGGAGCCGGCCCAGUUGUGAACUAGGAGAGCUUUGGGACCUCUGUCCCAAGCAAGUAAGAACUUUAGCCUUAGGAGAUGUAAAUAAAGUAGUAUUUGAAGAAGCACAGGAGAGAUGAAUGGAGAGUAUAGAGGCAGAGGAUUUGGACGAGGAAGAUUUCAAAGCUGGAAAAGGGGAAGAGGUGGUGGGAACUUCUCAGGAAAAUGGAGAGAAAGAGAACACAGACCUGAUCUGAGUAAAACCACAGGAAAACGUACUUCUGAACAAACCCCACAGUUUUUGCUUUCAACAAAGACCCCACAGUCAAUGCAGUCAACAUUGGAUCGAUUCAUACCAUAUAAAGGCUGGAAGCUUUAUUUCUCUGAAGUUUACAGCGAUAGCUCUCCUUUGAUUGAGAAGAUUCAAGCAUUUGAAAAAUUUUUCACAAGGCAUAUUGAUUUGUAUGACAAGGAUGAAAUAGAAAGAAAGGGAAGUAUUUUGGUAGAUUUUAAAGAACUGACAGAAGGUGGUGAAGUAACUAACUUGAUACCAGAUAUAGCAACUGAACUAAGAGAUGCACCUGAGAAAACCUUGGCUUGCAUGGGUUUGGCAAUACAUCAGGUGUUAACUAAGGACCUUGAAAGGCAUGCAGCUGAGUUACAAGCCCAGGAAGGAUUGUCUAAUGAUGGAGAAACAAUGGUAAAUGUGCCACAUAUUCAUGCAAGGGUGUACAACUAUGAGCCUUUGACACAGCUCAAGAAUGUCAGAGCAAAUUACUAUGGAAAAUACAUUGCUCUAAGAGGGACAGUGGUUCGUGUCAGUAAUAUAAAGCCUCUUUGCACCAAGAUGGCUUUUCUUUGUGCUGCAUGUGGAGAAAUUCAGAGCUUUCCUCUUCCAGAUGGAAAAUACAGUCUUCCCACAAAGUGUCCUGUGCCUGUGUGUCGAGGCAGGUCAUUUACUGCUCUCCGCAGCUCUCCUCUCACAGUUACGAUGGACUGGCAGUCAAUCAAAAUCCAGGAAUUGAUGUCUGAUGAUCAGAGAGAAGCAGGUCGGAUUCCACGAACAAUAGAAUGUGAGCUUGUUCAUGAUCUUGUGGAUAGCUGUGUCCCGGGAGACACAGUGACUAUUACUGGAAUUGUCAAAGUCUCAAAUGCGGAAGAAGGUUCUCGAAAUAAGAAUGACAAGUGUAUGUUCCUUUUGUAUAUUGAAGCAAAUUCUAUUAGUAAUAGCAAAGGACAGAAAACAAAGAGUUCUGAGGAUGGGUGUAAGCAUGGAAUGUUGAUGGAGUUCUCACUUAAAGACCUUUAUGCCAUCCAAGAGAUUCAAGCUGAAGAAAACCUGUUUAAACUCAUUGUCAAAUGGAGUCUUGCUCUGUCGCCCAGGCUAGAGUACAGUGGUGCGAUCUCAGCUCACUGCAACCUCCACCUCCCAAGUUCAAACAGUUCUCCCACCUCAGCCUGCCGAGUAGCUGGGACUACAGGCAUGCGCCACCAGACCCAGCUACUUUUGCUUGUUAAAGCAGGUUUGGCAUUAGCACUCUUUGGAGGAAGCCAGAAAUACGCAGAUGACAAAAACAGAAUUCCAAUUCGGGGAGACCCCCACAUCCUUGUUGUUGGAGAUCCAGGCCUAGGAAAAAGUCAAAUGCUACAGGCAGCGUGCAAUGUUGCCCCACGUGGCGUGUAUGUUUGUGGUAACACCACGACCACCUCUGGUCUGACGGUAACUCUUUCAAAAGAUAGUUCCUCUGGAGAUUUUGCUUUGGAAGCUGGUGCCCUGGUACUUGGUGAUCAAGGUAUUUGUGGAAUCGAUGAAUUUGAUAAGAUGGGGAAUCAACAUCAAGCCUUGUUGGAAGCCAUGGAGCAGCAAAGUAUUAGUCUUGCUAAGGCUGGUGUGGUUUGUAGCCUUCCUGCAAGAACUUCCAUUAUUGCUGCUGCAAAUCCAGUUGGAGGACAUUACAAUAAAGCCAAAACAGUUUCUGAGAAUUUAAAAAUGGGGAGUGCACUACUAUCCAGAUUUGAUUUGGUCUUUAUCCUGUUAGAUACUCCAAAUGAGCAUCAUGAUCACUUACUCUCUGAACAUGUGAUUGCAAUAAGAGCUGGAAAGCAGAGAACCAUUAGCAGUGCCACAGUAGCUCGUAUGAAUAGUCAAGAUUCAAAUACUUCCGUACUUGAAGUAGUUUCUGAGAAGCCAUUAUCAGAAAGACUAAAGGUGGUUCCUGGAGAAACAAUAGAUCCCAUUCCCCACCAGCUAUUGAGAAAGUACAUUGGCUAUGCUCGGCAGUAUGUGUACCCAAGGCUAUCCACAGAAGCUGCUCGAGUUCUUCAAGAUUUUUACCUUGAGCUCCGGAAACAGAGCCAGAGGUUAAAUAGCUCACCAAUCACUACCAGGCAGCUGGAAUCUUUGAUUCGUCUGACAGAGGCACGAGCAAGGUUGGAAUUGAGAGAGGAAGCAACCAAAGAAGACGCUGAGGAUAUAGUGGAAAUUAUGAAAUAUAGCAUGCUAGGAACUUACUCUGAUGAAUUUGGGAACCUAGAUUUUGAGCGAUCCCAGCAUGGUUCUGGAAUGAGCAACAGGUCAACAGCGAAAAGAUUUAUUUCUGCUCUCAACAACGUUGCUGAAAGAACUUAUAAUAAUAUAUUUCAAUUUCAUCAACUUCGGCAGAUUGCCAAAGAACUAAACAUUCAGGUUGCUGAUUUUGAAAAUUUUAUUGGAUCACUAAAUGACCAGGGUUACCUCUUGAAAAAAGGCCCAAAAGUUUACCAGCUUCAAACUAUGUAAAAGGACUUCACCAAGUUAGGGCCUCCUGGGUUUAUUGCAGAUUAAAGCCAUCUCAGUGAAGAUAUGCGUGCACGCACAGACAGACAGACACACACACACACACACACACACACACACACACACACACACACAGUCAAAUACUGUUCUCUGAAAAAUGAUGUCCCAAAAGUAUUAUAAUAGGAAAAAAGCAUUAAAUAUAAUAAACUAAUUUAAGAAGUGAUAAAGUCUCCAGAUGCAGUAGCUCACACUGUAAUCACAGUGACUCAGGAGGCUGAGGUGAGAGGAUUCCUUGAGGCCAGGGUUCGAGACCAACCUUGGGCAACAUAGCAAGACCCCAUUUCUUAAAAAAAAAAAAAAAAAAUUUAAACUUAGCUGGGUAUGGUGGCACAUGCCUAUAGUCUCAGCUACUUGUGAGGCUGAGGCAGGAGGAUUCUUUGAGCCCAGGAGUUUGAGGUUACAGUGAGCCACAAUCACACCAAUCACUGCACUCCAGCCUGGGCAAUAAAGUAACUCUUGACUCAAAAAAAUAAAAAAAAUUGUAGUGGUAGCCAUGUGUUAAUUGUUAAAUAAAUUCUCCAAAGGGCUAAAAGUAAAUUACUUAUAAAUUUUUUAUAGUUGUAUUUUUGACCUGCCUUUUAUAUGUAUGAAUAUUUCAUAGUUUUGCAUAUCAGAUGUAGGCAUACAGACAAAUACAUAAACCAAUGAAUAUAUUACAUAUUCUGUGUUCCAAUAAAACUUUAUUUAUGGACACUAAAAUUUGAAUUUCAUAAAAUUUUCCCAUGUCAAGAAUACAAAAUACUUGAGUUUUGUUUUUAGCUAUUUAAUAAUAGGUCUCAUUUAUUCCACAGGCUGUAGUUUGUAGUCUUGCUUGAAACAAUAGAAACAGACUGAUUAAGCAGGAGAAGUUUUUUGAAAGAAUUUUGUUUGGCUCACGGAAUUAUUAGAAGGCAGGUGAACCAGGAGGGUAAGCUUCCAGCAGCAAUUUGUAAAACCAUGCCUUAGAAUUGGACUAAGGAAGAAGCUGCUGACACUCCACUGCCACACAGGGCACUGGAAGAAAGUGCUGCUGCCUCCCUGCCCCACCUUUGCCACUUCUGCAGCAGGAAUAGGUAGAAGAAUGCCCCCACCCGCACCGGAACAGCAACAAAAGGAUUCUGCAUGAGAUGCCUCCCUAAAUUGCUGAAUUCAAAAAAGAAGUUGCAUACAAAGACAUCUGAUUGAAAAAGGGUAUGUUAUAUGCCCCUUUCAUAGGCUGCUAGGGAGUUUUCCUGGUUCUACUUUCAGGUGGUGGGAUCAAUAAGACCAGAAUUUCUCAUAUGUUGUGAGAGGAUUCAAAUGUUACAGGGUUGCCAGCCAAACUAUCAAUCAUGUAUAAAUCCAACAAACACUUUGUAACAUACAAGAACUCAGGAAAUGUGAACCAUUGUUGGAGAAUCUACUAAAAUACGGCUUCCCGCAAACGAAGAUGAAUGGAAAAUGUAAAUAAAAAGAACUGGCAGUGUAUAUCAGAUGUUUAACUAUAGGACCAGAACUAAGAUGUGGAGACUAUUGCCAUAGACCACAAUGUAAAUUUUUAAGUGAGGAAGGAAAAAUCAGGAAUCAAAAGGGGCCAGGUGCAGUGGCUCACAUCUAUAAUCCCAGAGCUUUGGGAGUUCGAGGCAGGAGGAUCACUUGAAGCCAGUUUUGAGACCAGCCUAUGCAACACAUUGAGACCCUAUCUCUACAAAAAAUAGAUUAGCUGGGCACGGUGGUGCAUGCCUAUUGUCCUACCUACUGUGGAGGCUGAAGUAGGAAAUCACUUGAGCCCGAGAGUUUGAGGUUACAGUGAGCUAUGAUUAUACCACUGCACUCCAGCCUGGGCAAGAGAGCAAGACCUUGUCUCUUAAAGAAAAAAAAAAAAAAUGGAGAAAGUAGAUAGUAGUAUAAAUAUAGUGAAGUCUUUAAAAGCUAGGAGUUAAAAGAUAUUUAAAGCAAAUAACUCAGGCAUGGUGGUGUGUGCCUGUAGUCCCAGCCACUAAGGAGGCUGAGGCAGGAGAAUCACUUGAACCCGGGAGGCAGAGGUUGCAGUGAGCCAAGAUCGUACCACUGCACUCCAGCCUGGGCAACAGAGUGAGACUCUUUCUCCAAACUAAAUAAGAGAUAUUUAAAGCUGAAAAAAAAUCUAUUAAUAGAAUUUAAAACAUUUCACAAAAGUCAACACAUAAAUAAUAUCAACCAAAAUAAAGUGGUAGACAGAAGAGAAAAUAUACUAAUUUAUUGUUCAAAGAGGAAAAUAAGUCUCAAAGGUUAAGGCUAUUAUAUAAAUUUAUUUUUAAAAAGACAUAAACCUACAUUUUCAGAAGAAGAAGUUCCAUGUUUCCUUAGAUUAUGUAUUUAGCAUCCAUUAAUCACAGGGCCAAACUAACAACAAAAGUUGUUUAGCUUUCCCUUACAAUCCAGCUUUUAUGGGUGUGCAAACAUCACAUUACAGUCCCUCCAACCACAAACCCCAACAUAUAGUAUUUCACUUCCUGCCCAAUAGUGGGUGUCCCCACACCUUUCAACCACUGUAGCAACAAAGCUCUGGCCUAGGCUUUUCACUUGCUUCUUUACUGCCUGACUGACUUUGGUGUUUCCUCAUGUGGCCUGGUGUGGCAUGGCACGCCCUCUUGGGAGAUGAAAGUAAUCUUCCAUAGGCAAUUGUUUCUGUGUCACCAUUGCUGAUUAAAACAAAUCCUAAGUACAAAUGUCAGAACAGAAACAUGCAAAGCAAGAAAACAUUACAUCAUGAAAGUUUCUUUUUUUUUCUUUUUUCUUUUUUUUUUUUUUUUGAGACAGAGUUUUGCUCUUUUUGCUCAGGCUGGAGUACAGUGGCGCGAUCUUGGUUCACCGCAACCUCCGCCUCCUGGGUUCAAGCGUUUCUCCUGCCUCAGCCUCCCAAGUAGCUGGGAUUAUAGGCAUGUGCCACCAUGGCUAAUUUUGUAUUUUUAGUAGAGACGGGGUUUCUCCAUGUUGGUGAGGCUGGUUUUUAACUCCCGAACUCAGGUGAUUGCCUGCCUCGGUCUCCCAAAAAGUGCCGGGAUUACAGGCGUGAGCCAUUGUGCCCAGCCAAAAGUUUCUUUUUCAAGAGAUGGUGGUCUUGCCAUGUUGUCCAGUAUGGACUUGAACUACUCAGCUCAAGCAGUCCUCCCACCUCAGCCUCCUGAAUAGCUGAGACUACAGGCAUGCACCACUACACCUGGCUGCGAGAUGAAAUUUUAAGAGAUGGGGGUCUUGUUCUGUCGCCCAGGCUGGAGUGCAGUGACAUGAUCAAGCCGUGAUCUCCUGGGCUCAAGCAAUCCUCCUACCUCAGCCUCCUGAGUAGCUGGAACUACAGGAAUGCAACACCAUGCCCAGCUAAUUUUGAUUUUUAGUAGAGAUGAGGUCUUCCUUUGUUGCCCAAGCUGGUCUCAAACUCCAGGGCUUCCUGAGUAGCUGAGACUACAGGUGUGAGCCACCAUGCCCAGCCUCCUCUCUUUUCCAAUAUUGUGUUAAGUAAAUUGUAUUGGUGGUAAUCAACUUGAUCAUUUCAUUUUUAGGAUAGAGAUAUCAAGGUGAGGGUAUAACUGAACGAGAAGAGGAAUAAACACCACCCUGUGAUUGAUGGAUCUUUAUAGCUCUCCUUUGAUAAAGAAGGGAAAUAUCGUACUUACAUUAGCAUGUUAUAGUUGCUGUUGUUAUACAGAAGAAUAUUAAACAAUAUUCAUAUAUUGUUUAUGAAUGCAUUGAAUUCAUAAACAAUGGUAUGGAUAUUGACUAGCCAAAGAGGUGGAUAAAUGUAGAUACAAUGAUACGGUGAUUUGGUAUUCAGUGUCCAUUCUGCUCUCCUAGUGUGCCUUCCUAUAAUGCAGGGGCUGGAAGGUGAGAAAAUAACCACAUUUCCCAGACUCCCUUUGCAGGUAGAUUUCCAGAUGUGAAUUGGGUUCCACUGAUCAGACACCCAUGUGUGAGAUUUGGAAUGCAGAACUGAGGAGAGAGCCAUCUUCCUCUUGCUUGUGUUCUGGUGGCAUGUGUGGUUGAGGAGACAUUUAAUUUCCCUGCAGCAGAAUUCUUGCAGUCAGUUGUUGAGGCAAGUGGCGUGGUGGAUGCAACCCUGAUUCUUCACCUUUCUCAUUAUUGUGGGGUAGCAGCGCCUCUGGCAAGCCAGACAGACCUGCAGUGUUUUUCUGGGAGUUAAUUCUGGAGACCCAGUAUGGAACCCACUCCUAGCCCUUGUGACAAUAUUGCAAGCAUCCAGUUCCCUGUUUUACAGUCCUUUUAAAUGUGGCUAGCUACAGUAGUUUGUGUUUCCUGCAACUAAUCACUCAUACAUCUGUAUCUAAAGCACUCCACCUGGGUCAUGUACUAUACUUAAAAUUAUAAGGCAAUAUUAAUUCACAAAACUACCUACUCGUUUUAUUUAACCCUCAGAAGAACUGAAAACAAAAGCUAUACCAGGCUUGCUCUAGAGCGUGGGCUUGGGAAUGGAAAGGCAGAGUGCACCUAUUGAAUUCCAUCAUCAGUUUUUCUAUACCAUGGAGUUACUUACCAUGUGUAUACAUAACACUGAUUAAAAAUUUUAAAAAAAA